GCGGGGGAAGGGGGCGGGGGCAGGGACGCACCCCCAGCACCUUCCCCACCUGUCUUCUCCUCCCCCACAAUCCCCAGACUCCAGAGCUAACCCAAUCAGAGACACCCCCUGAGAUUCCACCCCCAGGACCCUUAACCCUGCCUGGAAACACCCCCUCAUCCUCCUGUUUCUGUCCUUCAAACCCAGUAACCCACCCCCAUCCCUUCUCUGCCAUCUCUGCCCCUCAGCGCCCCAGAUCCCAAAUCAGGACACUUCCUUCUUCUCCUACCAACCCCAGAUCUCUGAGAUCUGGCCCCCAUGGCCCGCCUACAACCCUGGGCACCCCUCUUUUCCCGCCUUAUCCCCCAACGGUACCCCUCUUUUCCCACCUUAUCCCCCAACGGUACCCCUCUUUUCCCACCUUAUCCCCCAACGGUACCCCUCUUUUCCUACCGCAUCUUUAUUCGCCAAUCAGGGCACCCCAUUCAGUCUUCAAUCCUCUCUUCGGCCCCCCGCUUGGGGACACCCUGUCUCCCUCCAUCGUAGCCUCUAGAGACUCACACUACCCCAUUCCUGCUCUCCAGAUCCCUACCGUACACCCCAAGUAAAUAACUCCCCCAUCUCUCCAGAUUCCAGCUCAAGACACCCCUUUUUUCCCCAUUCAUUCCUGCCCUCGAGCCUCCAGAUUCCACCUGUUCCUUGGGGACCCCUCUCUACUCCUCCAGAUUCCUCUUUCGGGGCUGCCCGUCUUCUCCUGGCUUGCCGCAGGGAUUACUGAAAUGCCAGGGUCCCUCCUCCUCCCCACCUCAUCCCCCUGACCUAUCCUAUCUCUUCCCAUAGGAAAACAGCAGGGGCGGAGCCUGGGUGGUGGUCCCUGGACAGGUGCACCUAGAAGCUCUCUUCUGUGGCUUCUGGUGGCACUGACAGGAUGUCCCAGAGCUGGGGCCCUUUAAGUCCCCUUUUUCAGCUUCAGUGUGGGCCCCCAAGGAACUGGAGACAUGGCCCAGACUUGAACAGGAAGCACACACGGGCUCUAUCCUCUGUCCAGCUUCAGGGGGCGUUCUUUCCUGCCCGGCCUCUCUGGAGUUAGGAAGUCGGCCUGGACGGAUGGGUUUGGGCCAAGUGUGGAUGGGCAGGCUCUGAUUCAUGGACUGGAAAAUCCCUCCUUAGUCAUUUGCCAACUGUCCCUGAGGCCUGGGCUGGUCAUUGCCUCUCCCACUUCCCCUAGAAACCCAGGUGGAGUAGGGGCUAAGGAGGGCCCCUUCAUUGCAUGUGAGACACACAGAACAAUCUGAAAACCAUCUCCGAGCCUCCCACAAACCUGCCCUGGCCAAGCCGAGCCCUCAGAGUUCUUGACCCACAGAAGCUCAUGGAAUCCCCUGCAACCCUUUGGCAGUUGUUCUUGUUCCCACUUUGAGGAAACUGGGGCACAGAGAAGUUGAGAAACUUGCCCAAGGUCACCCAGCCAGGGAAUAGCAAGUCCAGAUUGGAAGGCAGGCUCAGCCAGCUCACUGUAUUGCCCAGAGCCCACAGCGGUGGCCAGGACACCCCCUCCCCUCCUGGGGCCCCUUCCCAGGGAUGGGGCAUGGAAGGGAAACUGAGGAACGACAGAGUCUGUCUUAGGAGUUGAAACAACUCACAGCUCUGGGACCCUGAACAAGUGAAUUCAUCCCACUAAGUCUCAGAUUCUCCCAGCUAUAAAACAGGUUCAUGAUUUAGUAUCAAUGUGCCAUCAAGGGUGUUCAAUCUUUUAGCUUCCCUAGGCCACACUGGAAGAAGAACUGUCUUGGGCCACAUAUAAAAUGCACUAACACUAACAAUAGCUGAUGAGCUUAAAAAGAAAAGAAAAGAAAAUCUUUGUAUUUAUUUAUUUAUUUAUUUAUCUGAAACGAGUCUCAGUCUGUUGCCAAGGCUGGAGUGCAGUGGCACGAUCUCGGCUCACUGUAGCCUCCACCUCCUGGGUUCAAGCAAUUCUCCCGCCUCAGCCUCCUGAGUAGCUGGGACUACAGGUGUGAGCCGCCAUACCCAGCUAAUUUUUGUAUAUUUAGUAGAGAUGGGGUUUCACCAUGUUGGCCAGGCUGGUUUCAAACUCCUGACCUCAAGUGAUCCUCCCACCUUGGCCUCCCUCCCAAAGUGUUGGAAUUACAGGCAUGAGCCACCGCACCCGGACGUAUCUUAUAAUGUUUUAAGAAAGCUUACGAAUUUGUGUUGGCCUGCAUUCAAAGCUCUCCUGGGCCAGGGCCGUGGGGCGUGGGUUGGACAAGCUCACACUAGGUGGCUGUGAGAAUUUGGAAAUUACAUACAUAAAGUGUUCAGCAUAGUGUGUGCAUUCUUUUCUUUUCUUUUCUUUUUUCUUUUCUUUUGAGGCAGAGCCUUGCUCAGUAGCCCAGUGAAACAAUGAUUGCGCAAUGACACAAUCAUAACUCACUGCAGCCUCAAACUCCUGGGCUCAAGCAAUCCUCCUGCCUCAGCCUCUUGAGUAGCUGGGAUUCCAGACGCCCACCACCACACCUGGCUAAUUUUUAAUUCUGUGUGUGUGUGUGUAGACAUGGGGUCUCACUAUGUUGCUCACGCUGGUCUGGAACGCCUGAGCUCAGGCAAUGCUGCCGCCUCAGCCUCCCAAAGUGCUGAGAUUACAGGUGUCCAGCCAAGAUGGGCACCUUAAUCAUUAUUAUCACUUUUUUCUAACUUCUUCCUGCUCCACCAAAGCCUGGUGGGUGGGAAGAUCUCACAACAGAAUCCCAAGACCCUGCAGCUAGGAGGAUCCAGGAGGGAAACCGCAAGAAAGUUCUAGAAUGCUAACUAUGGGCCAGGUGUUAUUGUGGAGGAGCGGUUCUCCCGGGUGCCUGAGCCCGUCCAGAAGCGCAUCGUGUUUUGGUCGUUUCCACGCAGUGAACGGGAAAUAUGUAUGUACUCGUCGCUGGGUUACCCGCCCCCAGAGGGCGAGCACGAUGCCCGGGUGCCCUUUACCCGCGGGCUGCACCUGCUCCAGAGCGGGGCCGUGGACCGCGUGUUGCAAGUGGGAUUCCACCUGAGCGGAAACAUCCGCGAGCCAGGGAGUCCUGGAGAGCCCGAGCGCCUCUACCAUGUCUCCAUCAGCUUUGAUCGCUGCAAGAUCACGUCCGUGAGCUGCGGCUGUGACAACCGCGACCUCUUCUACUGUGCCCACGUGGUGGCCCUGUCCCUGUACCGCAUUCGGCACGCCCACCAGGUGGAGCUGCGGCUGCCCAUCUCCGAGACGCUCUCCCAGAUGAACCGGGACCAGCUGCAGAAGUUCGUGCAGUACCUCAUCAGCGCCCAUCACACUGAGGUGCUGCCCACUGCUCAGCGCUUGGCUGAUGAGAUCCUCCUGCUGGGCUCCGAGAUCAACUUGGUGAAUGGUGCCCCAGACCCCACCGCCGGCGCAGGAAUCGAGGACGCCAACUGCUGGCACCUGGACGAGGAGCAGAUCCAGGAGCAGGUGAAGCAGCUACUGUCCAAUGGCGGCUACUACGGGGCCAGCCAGCAGCUGCGCUCCAUGUUCAGCAAGGUGCGGGAGAUGCUGCGAAUGCGGGACUCCAACGGGGCGCGCAUGCUGAUUCUCAUGACCGAGCAGUUCCUGCAGGACACGCGCCUGGCCCUGUGGCGGCAGCAGGGCGCGGGCAUGACGGACAAGUGCCGGCAGCUCUGGGAUGAGCUGGGGGCCCUGUGGGUUUGCGUCGUCCUGAGCCCCCACUGCAAACCAGAGGAAAGGGCAGGCUGGCUCCAGCUACUCAGCAGGUGGGACAAGCUCGACGUCUGCCCACUGGAAGAGGGCAACUACUCCUUCGACGGCCCCAGCCUGCAGCCCACCAUGGCCCCCGCCCCAGGCUCGGAGGAAGAGGAAGAGGUGGCAGCCACAAGUCCCCGCCACACGGUAUUUGGCCGCGCCUUGCUGGCUGGAGAGCUACACUGGAAUGACGCCUACCUGCAGAGGAUCCUGGCCAGUGACUCCUACGGGCCCAGCCUCACAGGCAGCGUGGGUGGGGACAAACCGACUUUCGACCCCCAGGGCCGCCCACUGUGGCUGGGAGAACCUUUCCCCACUGCCUGUGCCCGUGUGGACACCCUGCGUGCCCACGGAUACCCCCGCCAGGCCCUGCGGCUGGCAAGUGCCAUCAUCAACACACUCCGGCUGCAGCAGCGGCAUCAGCUAGAGAGCUACAAGCAGCAGAAAAAAGAGACUUGGGCAGGUGUGUGGGCAUUGAGCCCCCUCUUUCCACCUGCAGAGCUGCUCCAGAAGGGCUCCACCUGCAUCACCAACACCGAAGGAUGGGUGGGGCACCCCCUGGACCCCAUUGGCUGCCUCUGCAGGGCGCUCCUGGAGGCCUGUCGUCUGGAGGAGGAGACACUUACCCUUUACCCAGACUCAGGCCCCGAGAAGCGGAAGGUGGCCUACCAGCACGUGCCUGUGCCCGGGAGCCCUGGGGAGUCCUACUUGGUGCUGGCGCUGGAGGUGGCACUGCUGGGGCUGGGGCAGCAGCGGGCCCUGCCGGAGGGGCUGUACGCCCAGGACAAGGUGGUGCGCAACGAGGAGCAGCUGCUGGCCCUGCUGGAGGAGGUGGAGUUGGAUGAGCGGUUGGUGCAGGUGCUGCGCAAGCAGGCGGGGCUGCUGCUGGAAGGGGGUCCCUUCAGUGGCUUUGGGGAGGUGCUGUUCCGGGAGAGCGUGCCCAUGCACACCUGUGCCCGCUACCUGUUCACCGCACUGCUGCCUCAUGACCCGGACCUGGCCUAUCGCCUCGCGCUGCGAGCUAUGAGGCUGCCCAUACUGGAGACAGCAUUUCCUGCUGGAGAACCUCAUCCCAGCCCGCUGGACUCCAUCAUGAGCAACCGCUUCCCCCGCUGGUUCAUCCUUGGCCACCUGGAGACCCGCCAGUGUGAACUGGCUUCCACCAUGUUGACGGCCGCCAAGGGAGACCCCAAGUGGCUGCACACGGUACUGGGCUCCAUCCAGCAGAACAUCCACUCUCCGGCCCUGCUCUUUAAGCUGGCGCAGGACGCCUGCAAGACAGCCACCCCGGUCAGCGCCCCACCAGACACCACGCUGCUGGGCAUCGCACUGGAGCUGGGGCUGCAGGUGAUGCGGAUGACUCUGAACGUAAUGACCUGGCGGCGGAGGGAGAUGGUGCGCUGGCUGGUCAGCUGUGCCACAGAGAUUGGCCCGCAAGCCCUGAUGAAUAUCAUGCAGAACUGGUAUUCCUUAUUCACACCAGUGGAGGCGGCUACCAUCGUGGCAGUGACGGGCACCACACACGCCACUCUGCUGCGACUGCAGCUGGACACAUCGCGGAGGGAGGAGCUCUGGGCCUGCGCCCGCACCCUGGCCUUGCAGUGCGCGAUGAAGGACCCUCAGAACUGCGCCUUGCCUGCCCUGACCCUGUGCGAGAAGAACCACUCGGCCUUCGAGGCGGCCUACCAGAUCGUGCUGGACGCGGCGGCCGGCGGCCUGGGCCACGCCCACCUCUUCACUGUGGCCCGCUAUAUGGAGCACCGCGGGCUGCCGCUCCGGGCCUACAAGCUGGCGACGCUGGCCCUGGCGCAGCUCAGCAUCGCCUUCAACCAGGACAGCCACCCUGCCGUCAACGACGUGCUUUGGGCCUGCUCUCUCAGCCACUCCCUGGGCCGGCACGAGCUCUCUGCCAUCGUCCCCCUCAUCAUUCGCAGCAUCCACUGUGCCCCAAUGCUGUCCGAUAUUCUGCGCCGCUGGACUCUCUCGGCGCCCGGUCUGGGCCCCUUAGGGGCACGCCGGGCCGCCAAGCCACUGGGUGCCGACCGGGCGCCGCUCUGCCAGCUCCUGGACGCGGCAGUCACCGCCUACAUCACCACCAGCCACUCGCGCCUCACGCACAUCAGCCCGCGGCACUAUGGGGAUUUCAUCGAAUUCCUGGGCAAGGCCCGGGAGACCUUCCUGCUGGCGCCCGACGGGCACCUCCAGUUCUCACAGUUCUUGGAGAACCUCAAACAGACCUACAAGGGCAAGAAGAAACUCAUGCUUUUGGUGCGGGAGCGUUUUGGUUGAGGGACAGUGGGGUGCGUGGGAGUGGGGAUCCCCCUCGCCCCUGCGUCCCCCACCCUUGCUCUCCAAUUAGGCCCACGUGGCAUUUCAGUAUUAUUAAGUCAGGGAAGGAGCCCGGCUGGAGAUGGGGGCAGGGGGAGCAGCAUCCUGCCACGUGUGUGCCUGGGAGUCUGUGAGCAAGUGUGCAAGACUCCAGAAGCAGAAGCCAUACUGCCACCCAGAAGCCUGGAAGGGGUGUGUGCUUGGGCUGCUGGUAUGACCCCACUUUGGGCACCCCAAAAGCAAUAGGCAAACUCCCCUUACCCAGACUGGCUUGGGCUCCAGGAGGGAGGCUGGGAGGCAGGACUUUCCAGAAAUCGACCCUCUAAGUCAAUGUAGCACAUUUUCCCCCAACCCCACCCUGGGUGGCCAAGGGUCCUCCCCCACCCCCUACUGCUCAGGGCCCCCCAUUAUGCCACCUCCAAAGUGGCUGCCCAGCCAGGACCAUUGGCUCACCCCCACUGAAGGAAUUGAAGAGGCCUCAGGCCUCAGCCUCAUACCUCACCCCCUUAUCCUAUCCGGCCAGGACCCCCAUUUCCUUGGGCACUAGGGUCCCAGGGUGGGCUCAGGGUUGGGGAAGUCCUCGCUGCCCUCUCUUCUCACCUGCUAGUCACUGGACGUACAACUCAGGAACUGAGCGAGGCUCACACUGCCCCUUCCAACCUGGGGUUGGGGGACACAGACGCGAGAGAGCCGGAGACCCCCACCCCCGAUCUGGAAAGGAAAGAGACCUGUAUCUUGGUGUUUUUCUGGCUUUUUCACCCUUUCGCCUCCUGUCUUUCUGCUUCGCCCCUUCAUCUUACUCUGUUUCCAUUUUUCCCGGCACUUACCUGCCUUUCUCUCUGCACCUAAGUCCCUGCCGCCCUCUCUCUUUGGCCAUCCUUCCUUUCCCCCACCUUGACCCAGGGAGGAGAAGGGAGAACAUCACCCCCCCAAGUCACCCCCACAUCUUUUCCCUUCUUGUAUAUUAAGGACAAAAUACCACAUCAUUUUGUAACUUUUUUUCUAUUUAUUGAACGGUGUAUUACAUGUCCUUUUCCUUUUUUUUUUUCAAAGAUUGAACAGAAAUUUUUCUUUUUAAUUUUAUUUUGAGACUGGGGUGCAUCUCCAGAGCCACUCACACCCUCAACCUCGUUUCCUCCGCAAAAAAAAAAAAAAAAAAAAAAAA